GGACCAACUUAGGUCAGUUGUCUGACCCUGUAACAGUUGUCAGAGGAAUGCCAUGAUCUGAUUGGCUUAGACUAAACAGGAUCAACCCAGGGUGGCGUCACUUAAUCACAGGGGAGAGGAAUGCAUUCAUGAACACAAUGGAGUUCUUUUAGGAAGGAAGAGGGAGAAUAGAGACUGGAUAUGCAACCAACAAUGUCCAUGACGGAGAUAUAAGCUAGAUGAGAUAUGAGUUAGUUACAUAUCAUGAGUCGUGUUCACUGAUUUGGGCACUUUGGAAAGCUUUCAUGAUCCUUAUACUUUAGGUUUACUGAUGGAAGUGAAGGGUAGAUUAACCUGGGUUGGUGACUGAGGGCCAAGUAAGUGGACACUAUGAUGGUUGAUAAGCUUGACUAUCAAGGGAAGGAGAGAGAAUUUGGUAACUAGAAGGAUAUGUUCAGUCAAGAUUCUAGAGAGAAUACCUCAGCUGUGCAAGGGAGAGAUAUUCCCACCCGAGAGAUGGAAGGAAAAGAAAGGUGCGAGAGAUUGUAGACCAGUGGUUCUCCAUAGAAUGGUACGACUCAACAGAAUGGUAAUUCAGAGGUCCGUGGGGCCAGCCAGCCUGAGCUUGCUCACCUUCAAAGUCUAUGCAGCACCAAAAAAGGACUCACCUCCCAAAAAUUCCGUGAAGGUUGAUGAGCUUUCACUCUACUCAGUUCCUGAGGGUCAAUCGAAGUAUGUGGAGGAGGCAAGGAGCCAGCUUGAAGAAAGCAUCUCACAGCUCCGACACUAUUGCGAGCCAUACACAACCUGGUGUCAGGAAACGUACUCCCAAACUAAGCCCAAGAUGCAAAGUUUGGUUCAAUGGGGGUUAGACAGCUAUGACUAUCUCCAAAAUGCACCUCCUGGAUUUUUUCCGAGACUUGGUGUUAUUGGUUUUGCUGGCCUUAUUGGACUCCUUUUGGCUAGAGGUUCAAAAAUAAAGAAGCUAGUGUAUCCGCCUGGUUUCAUGGGAUUAGCUGCCUCCCUCUAUUAUCCACAACAAGCCAUCGUGUUUGCCCAGGUCAGUGGGGAGAGAUUAUAUGACUGGGGUUUACGAGGAUAUAUAGUCAUAGAAGAUUUGUGGAAGGAGAACUUUCAAAAGCCAGGAAAUGUGAAGAAUUCACCUGGAACUAAGUAGAAAACUCCAUGCUCUGCCAUCUUAAUCAGUUAUAGGAAAAACUAGACCAGACCUCUGUUAUCUUCUGUGAAAUCAUCCUACAAGCAAACUAACCUGGAAUCCCUUCACCUAGAGAUAAUGUACAAGCCUUAGAACUCCUCAUUCUCAUGUUGCUAUUUAUGUACCUAAUUAAAA